GGGGGCUCCUUGCUUCCAGUGAACACAGGCCCUGAGCCUUUACAGCCCUUCGUAUUUAUUAGAGUGAAUAGGGAGAAGGGGGGUGGUUGUCGGUCAGUAGCUUGAUUUACAGCAGGCUUGCAAGACUGCAUUCGUCAACCAAUAGGCUCUAGAUGUCCCAUUAGAUAACCUCAAGGAGCAUGACACCAGGGAGUGAUUGCCUUCAGCAAACCUUCUGGUGGCUGGAGCAGAAGCGACUUUGCCCACAUUCUGCAUUCAUGAUAAACAGUUUGCUGUUUGAUCAUAUAGCCUCCAGUGGAAUGUUGAGUUGGCCACGAUCCCUUUGCCAGCUCUCUACAGCUGUUCUACCUGUUGACAUCCUGUGUCAUACCCAAGCAGGAAGAAGGUUGUGUGAGAUGACAAAAGGCCAGAGUUACAUGCCAGCUGUGUCUCUUUCCACACAUCCACCAAACCCCCAGCAAAUGUGUACUUAAAAUUCAUUGGUUACAGAGCCACUACUCCUUACAAGGAGACUGGGGAGGUGAGUAUUAUAAGCUGGGCAGAUGGCCACUUGAAGAGCAUCAAUGUUCUGCUGUGGAAGGAGUGCAAAAUAGACACCAGAGAGACCAUUAGCAGUGUCUGCCACAGCUAUUACAUGGCUAGGUCCACCUGACUGAAACUAAGCCUUUUCUAUGAGACUGAAGUGCUUUGAGAGAAAUGCUGACCUUGUCCUUUCUGCAGCUUGCGGCUUUCAGUCACCCUUGGAUUCAGAGAUAGAAGUCAUCUUAAUUCCAUCACUGAGGCCAGGAGACCUGAAAGAAAUCAAUUCAAGAGUAAGGAGACCAGGCGUGCAGUGUGACUGGGCGUGCAGAGCUCUGCCUUCCAGGGACACUGCUCUUCCCCAGGAGAGAAACAAGAAGCUGGAGGCUGUGGGGACAGGAAUUGAACCUAAAGCCAUGUCCCAGGGCUUGGUGACAUUUGGGGAUGUGGCUGUAGAUUUCUCCCAAGAGGAGUGGGAGUGGCUGAACCCCAUUCAGAGGAACUUGUACAGGAAGGUGAUGUUGGAGAACUACAGGAACCUGGCAUCGCUGGGACUUUGUGUUUCUAAGCCCGAUGUGAUCUCCUCGUUGGAACAAGGAAAAGAGCCUUGGACAGUGAAGCGAAAGAUGACAAGAGCCUGGUGCCCAGACUUGAAGGCUGUGUGGAAGAUCAAGGAGUUACCUCUCAAGAAGGACUUCUGCGAAGGAAAGCUAUCCCAGGCAGUGAUAACAGAGAGACUCACAAGCUAUAAUCUGGAGUACUCUCUGUUAGGGGAACACUGGGAUUAUGAUGCUCUGUUUGAGACACAGCCGGGCUUGGUGACUAUCAAAAACCUGGCUGUUGACUUCCGCCAGCAGCUACACCCAGCUCAGAAGAAUUUCUGUAAGAAUGGGAUAUGGGAGAACAACAGUGACCUGGGAUCAGCAGGACAUUGUGUGGCUAAGCCAGAUUUAGUCUCUUUACUAGAGCAAGAGAAGGAGCCCUGGAUGGUGAAGCGAGAGCUGACAGGAAGCCUGUUCUCAGGCCAGCGAUCUGUACAUGAGACCCAGGAAUUAUUUCCAAAGCAAGAUUCAUAUGCUGAAGGGGUAACAGACAGAACCUCAAACACUAAACUUGAUUGUUCCAGUUUCAGAGAAAAUUGGGAUUCUGACUAUGUGUUUGGAAGGAAGCUUGCAGUAGGUCAAGAGACACAAUUCAGGCAAGAGCCAAUUACUCAUAACAAAACCCUCUCUAAGGAAAGAGAACGUACAUAUAACAAAUCUGGAAGAUGGUUCUAUUUGGACGAUUCAGAAGAGAAAGUUCAUAAUCGUGAUUCAAUUAAAAAUUUUCAAAAAAGUUCAGUGGUAAUAAAACAAACAGGCAUCUAUGCAGGAAAAAAGCUUUUCAAGUGUAAUGAAUGUAAGAAAACUUUUACCCAGAGCUCAUCUCUUACUGUUCAUCAGAGAAUUCACACUGGAGAGAAACCUUAUAAAUGUAAUGAAUGUGGGAAGGCCUUUAGUGACGGCUCAUCCUUUGCCCGACACCAGAGAUGUCACACUGGCAAGAAGCCCUAUGAGUGCAUUGAGUGUGGGAAAGCUUUCAUACAGAACACAUCCCUUAUCCGUCACUGGAGAUACUAUCAUACUGGGGAGAAACCCUUUGAUUGCAUCGAUUGUGGGAAAGCCUUCAGUGACCACAUAGGGCUUAAUCAACACAGGAGAAUUCAUACUGGAGAGAAACCUUACAAAUGUGAUGUAUGUCACAAAUCCUUCAGGUAUGGUUCCUCCCUUACUGUACAUCAAAGGAUUCAUACCGGAGAAAAACCAUAUGAAUGUGAUGUUUGCAGAAAAGCCUUCAGCCAUCAUGCAUCACUCACUCAACAUCAAAGAGUACAUUCUGGAGAAAAGCCUUUUAAGUGUAAAGAGUGCGGAAAAGCUUUUAGGCAGAAUAUACACCUUGCCAGUCAUUUAAGGAUUCAUACUGGGGAGAAGCCUUUUGAAUGUGCGGAGUGUGGAAAAUCCUUCAGCAUCAGUUCUCAGCUUGCCACUCAUCAGAGAAUCCAUACUGGAGAGAAGCCCUAUGAAUGUAAGGUUUGUAGUAAAGCGUUCACCCAGAAGGCUCACCUUGCACAGCAUCAGAAAACCCAUACAGGAGAGAAACCAUAUGAGUGCAAGGAAUGCGGUAAAGCCUUCAGCCAGACCACACACCUCAUUCAACAUCAGAGAGUUCACACUGGUGAGAAACCCUAUAAAUGUAUGGAAUGUGGGAAGGCCUUUGGUGAUAACUCAUCCUGUACUCAACAUCAAAGACUGCACACUGGCCAAAGACCUUAUGAAUGUAUUGAGUGUGGAAAGGCAUUCAAGACAAAAUCCUCCCUUAUUUGUCAUCGCAGAAGUCAUACUGGAGAAAAACCUUAUGAAUGCAGUGUGUGUGGCAAAGCCUUUAGUCAUCGUCAAUCCCUUAGUGUACAUCAGAGAAUCCAUUCUGGAAAGAAACCAUAUGAAUGUAAGGAAUGUAGGAAAACCUUCAUCCAAAUUGGACACCUUAAUCAACAUAAGAGAGUUCAUACUGGAGAGAGAUCUUAUAACUAUAAGAAAAGCAGAAAAGUCUUCAGGCAAACUGCUCACUUAGCUCAUCAUCAGCGAAUUCAUACUGGAGAGUCGUCAACAUGCCCCUCUUUACCUUCCACGUCAAAUCCUGUGGAUCUGUUUCCCAAAUUUCUCUGGAAUCCAUCCUCCCUCCCAUCACCAUAGCCUCGAGACGUCAUUUCUGUUUGACUACUCCAGCAGUUUAAAACCCCAUCUCCCUGCCCUUUUGUUUUCUUUUUGUCCCUUAUUAGUUAGUUCUUCACAUAAGUGUAAAUGUAACUUAUUCACUCCUCUUGUAAAACUUAUAGUUUCUUUAAAUUGGUUAAUGUGUGAGAUGUGCUCAGCACAGUGCCUGGUCCAUAGUAAGUGCUCAGUAAACUUAGCUGUUUUAAAAACUUUGUAUUUGAACAUUGAAAAGUUACAGUAGUCAGCUCUGAUAAAAAAAUGAUGCAGUAGGGUGAGGGUAGGAAAAAGCACAUUUUCUAUCAGGAACAGAAUUCUCCAGUAGUGGGUGAGGUUUUGCCUUUGUUGGUUUUAAAACUUGAUUCUAUAAUGCCAAGUUAGUUUUGUGGCUUUCCAUCUGACCCUAUGUGAAUGUAAGGUGAUGUGACCUUGUUGGUGAGAAAAUUAAACUUUACAUUUGACUUGAUUUGUUUUAGAAAGUCUAGGGACCAUGAAUGAAUAGGCCAGCUGGGACAAAUGAAUUUAAAAAAUCAGAAAAAUGCAAGAUUUAUAUGCAUGAAGUUAAAACAACUGACGUUACUCAAGAAUUAGAAAACUUUGCAAGAUUUGACUUGUUUAAAAAUCACAUUUAUAAGUGAACCGUAUUAAAACUUUUAAGGAACCAUUCAUUGUGAGGUAAACUGAUCCAGAAUAGGGGUCAGCAAACUAUGACUCAUGGCCACAGUCUCACUGACUGUUUUUGUAUGGUCCAUGAUCUAGAAUUUAAAAAAAUUUUAAAGGGUUGAAAAAAGUGAAAAGAAUAUUUUCAACAUGAAAAUUAUAUGAAAUUUAAGUUUUGGUGUCUGUAAAUAAAGUUUUGUUGGCUUCAGCCACACAGUGAUUUACACCUUGAUUGUGCUGCUUCCAGGCUGUAGCAGCAGAGUUGAGCAGUUGUGACAGGAGACCAUGUGGCCUGCAGAGCCCAAAUAUCUACUGUCUGAUCCUACACAGAAAAUGUGUGUGAUCCCUGCUAUGGAGCAGAGGUUAUCAAACUAAAGCCCAUGGACCAAAUCCUAUCUGCUGCUUGUUUUUGUAAAUAGAGUUUUAUCAAACCACAGCCAUGCUUACUUGUUUAGCUAUUGACUAUGGCUGCUUUAGACAACUGUGACAGACUAUAUGGCUCGCAAAACUGCAAAUAUUUCCUAUCCUUUAACAGAAAGUUUGCCAACCUCUGCUCUAGAGUAGAGAAAAAUGUAUAAAAGAUUUUAAUUUUAUGAGGGCAAUACAACUGUCACAUCAGAAACAAGAAAACAAAUGAUAAAGGAACUCAUUUAUCAAUAGAGGUGAAAGGAAAUUAUUAAACUAUAUUGAAAAAUAAAGAUGUCAAUAAAAGGAGAAAUGAUAUUUUUCUAGAUGAAA